AGUCCCCAGCGACUCGCAGGGGCUGGUGGGGCUGGGGUCCAGCUGCCGUGCUCCCCUGCCCUGCGCCGCGCCGCGCGUCUUGGUAGGCGCUGCGCUGCCGGGGCCGGGUCCUGGGCCAGUGCAACUCCGCCCCCAGCCGUAUCCAGCGGACUGUCCUCCGCCGCGCGCCCGGCACAGCAUGGGGAGGCGCUGCUGCCGGCGGCGCGUGCUGGCGGCCGCCUGUCUGGGCGCCGCGCUCCUGCUCCUAUGCGCCGCGCCCCGCUCCCUGCGCCCGGCAUUUGGAAACAGAGCCCUGGGCUCCAGCUGGCUUGGUGGGGAGAAGAGAAGCCCCCUGCAGAAGCUCUAUGACCUGGAUCAGGACCCGCGCUCGACCCUGGCGAAGGUGCACCGGCAGCGGCGCGACCUGCUGAACAGCGCCUGUAGCCGCCACUCACGCCGGCAGCGCCUGCUACAGCCGGAGGACCUGCGGCACGUGCUGGUGGACGACGCGCAUGGCCUGCUCUACUGCUACGUGCCCAAGGUGGCCUGCACCAACUGGAAGCGCGUGCUGCUGGCGCUGAGCGGCCAAGCCCGCGGCGACCCGCGCGCCAUCUCCGCGCAAGAGGCGCACGCGCCUGGCCGCCUGCCCUCACUGGCCGACUUCAGCCCCGCCGAGAUCAACCGGCGCCUGCGCGCCUACUUGGCCUUCCUGUUCGUGCGGGAGCCCUUCGAGCGCCUGGCAUCGGCUUACCGCAACAAGCUCGCGCGCCCCUACAGCGCCGCCUUCCAGAGGCGCUACGGUGCACGCAUCGUUCAGCGCCUGCGGCCGCGCGCGCUCCCCGACGCCCGGGCCCGCGGCCACGACGUGCGCUUCGCGGAGUUCCUGGCCUACCUGCUGGACCCGCGCACGCGGCGUGAGGAGCCCUUCAACGAGCACUGGGAGCGCGCGCACGCGCUCUGCCACCCGUGUCGCCUCCGCUACGACGUCGUGGGCAAGUUCGAGACGCUGGCGGAGGACGCGGCCUUCGUGCUGGGCCUGGCGGGCGCAUCCGACCUGAGCUUCCCUGGGCCGCCGCGGCCCCGGGGAGCCGCCGCCUCCCGCGACCUGGCAGCGCGCCUCUUCCGGGACAUCAGCCCCUUCUACCAGCGGCGCCUCUUCGACCUCUACAAGAUGGACUUCCUGCUUUUCAACUACUCCGCCCCCUCCUACCUGCGGCUGCUCUAGCGGUCCUGGAGGUCCUGUGGCCACGCGGGGCAAGUGCCUUUCCGACAAGACCCCCGGGGAAUGCAGGUGCUGCCGGCCCCAGGACCCCUCUUCAAGAGCCACUGCGUGCACUCACCUGGCCGCCGGGCCAGCGGGCGCAGGGCACACCUGGCCAGGCUUGGGGGCAGCCCAUCUCAGGUGGCCCUGCACGCGUGUGCCUGCCUCGGCCUGUCGCCUGAGGCCUGCUUCCUCCACUUGCUCCAGCUGACAGGCACCUCUCCAGGCCCCGUAGAUGGGCAAGGACUUGAUAACCAGGGUUUUAGGCUUUUAAAGGCCAUUUUGGGGGUCAGCCCUGCCCCUGAACCUGUUCAUGGUGCAUCAGAACAUAAUGCUGACACCGGUGUCAGUGUGGCCCGAGCCUGUGUCCUCCCCACCUCGCCCACCCUGGCAAGGACAGCUGCGGCCAAGGACGAAAGCCCUCCCUUGGCUGGCCUCACGAUGGGGCCGUCCCGGGAGCCAGGUGGGAGCUGCCUUCCACUGCCAUCGGGUCUCCUCUCCUCUCCCACGCGGCUGGCCCUACCCAGGCGCCACCUUCGGUCUCAGUCUGGCAAGACGCUGGGUCUUCAGGCUCCAUGCCAACAGAGCCCCUGGUGCAAUGCGGUCACAGGUUUUAUGGGACUUUGGUGAGCUGGGCGGUCAUGGUUUUGAAAUAAAUGUAUUUUGUUACUUUCUGA